GGGCGGGGCUCACGCGAGGCGCUGGAACGGUCCGGGAGAUUCUCGCUCUGCUGCUUUAGCUUCGGAGUGUUUGGCGAUGGGGCAGCGCGAGAUGUGGAGGCUCAUGUCGAGGUUUAAUGCAUUCAAAAGGACUAAUACCAUACUGCACCAUUUGAGAAUGUCCAAGCACACAGAUGCAGCAGAAGAGGUGCUAUUGGAAAAAAAAGGUUGCACGGGAGUCAUAACACUAAACAGACCAAAGUUCCUCAAUGCACUGACUCUUAAUAUGAUUCGGCAGAUUUAUCCACAGCUAAAGAAGUGGGAACAAGAUCCUGAAACUUUCCUGAUCAUUAUAAAGGGAGCAGGAGGAAAGGCUUUCUGUGCCGGGGGUGAUAUCAGAGUGAUCUCGGAAGCUGAAAAGGCAAAACAGAAGAUAGCUCCAGUUUUCUUCAGAGAAGAAUAUAUGCUGAAUAAUGCUGUUGGUUCUUGCCAGAAACCUUAUGUUGCACUUAUUCAUGGAAUUACAAUGGGUGGGGGAGUUGGUCUCUCAGUCCAUGGGCAAUUUCGAGUGGCUACAGAAAAGUGUCUUUUUGCUAUGCCAGAAACUGCAAUAGGACUGUUCCCUGAUGUGGGUGGAGGUUAUUUCUUGCCACGACUCCAAGGAAAACUUGGUUACUUCCUUGCAUUAACAGGAUUCAGACUAAAAGGAAGAGAUGUGUACAGAGCAGGAAUUGCUACACACUUUGUAGAUUCUGAAAAGUUGGCCAUGUUAGAGGAAGAUUUGUUAGCCUUGAAAUCUCCUUCAAAAGAAAAUAUUGCAUCUGUCUUAGAAAAUUACCAUACAGAGUCUAAGAUUGAUCGAGACAAGUCUUUUAUACUUGAGGAACACAUGGACAAAAUAAACAGUUGUUUUUCAGCCAAUACUGUGGAAGAAAUUAUUGAAAACUUACAGCAAGAUGGUUCAUCUUUUGCCCUAGAGCAAUUGAAGGUAAUUAAUAAAAUGUCUCCAACAUCUCUAAAGAUCACACUAAGGCAACUCAUGGAGGGGUCUUCAAAGACCUUGCAAGAAGUACUAACUAUGGAGUAUCGGCUAAGUCAAGCUUGUAUGAGAGGUCAUGACUUUCAUGAAGGCGUUAGAGCUGUUUUAAUUGAUAAAGACCAGAGUCCAAAAUGGAAACCAGCUGAUCUAAAAGAAGUUACUGAGGAAGAUUUGAAUAAUCACUUUAAGUCUUUGGGAAGCAGUGAUUUGAAAUUUUGAGGUGACAGGCUUUUAAGAAACUAAGUGAACUUCAGGUUUGUAAGAAUAAAAAGCCAACGGAACUGAAAAAGACAUUAAAGAUCAUGUCCUGCACCCUUCUCAUAGAUGAGGAAAUGGCAGCCCAGAAGGUAUUGCUUUAUGUUUUCUCAGUUCUUAAUCUGUUUUAUGUGAAGCAUUUUUCUUUCAAAUAAUUCAGUAACAGAUCUGGAAUAAAGAUGCCAUGAUAUCGGAUACAUUUACAUUUAUACUCUUAAAGGUCCUAAAUUGGACCUGAAUGAUCCAAGAAAUUAUUUGUAUAAAUGGAUUUUUGUUCUCUAUAUUUGUUAACAAUGCAGAAAAUGUUGUCUUUUAUAUUGUUAAAAAAUUCAAAGUACACACUGUCAGAAAGCAUUUGCUUCAGUUAAAUAAGAGCUCACACUAGUUAAUUGCAACUGGACUUUUAUUGUGCAGUUACAACAACAAAUGUUUUCAGAAAAAUAUUUGGAAAAAAUAUACCACUUCAUAGCUAAGUCUUACAGAGAAGAGGAUUUGCUAAUAAAACUUAAGUUUUGAAAAUUAAGAUGCAGGUAGUGCUUCUGAACUAAUGCCCACAGCUCCAAGGAAGACAUGUCCUAUUUAGUUAUUCAAAUACAAGUUGAGGGCAUUGUGAUUAAGCAAACAAUAUAUUUGUUAGAACUUUGUUUUUAAAUUACUGUUCCUUGACAUUACUUAUAAAGAGUCUCUAACUUUCGAUUUCUAAAACUAUGUAAUACAAAAGUAUAGUUUCCCCAUUUGAUAAAAGGCCAAUGAUACUGAGUAGGAUAUAUGCGUAUCAUGCUACUUCAUUCAGUGUGUCUGUUUUUAAUACUAAUAAGGCAGUUUGACAAAUUAUUUCUUUGGGACUAAGGUGAUUAUCAUUUUUUUCCCCUUCAAAAUUGUGCUUUAAGUGCUGAUAACCACAGGCAGAUUGCAAAGAACUGAUAAGGCAACAAAAGUAGAGAAUUUUAGGAUCAAAGGCAUGUAACUGAAAGGUAACAACAGUACAUAAGCGACAACUGGGGAAGGCAGCAGUGAAACAUGUUUGUGGGGUUAAGUGAGUCAUUGUAAAUAAGGAAUUUGCACAUUUAUUUUCUCUGAUAACCUGCUUCCAUGUUGCCACCUGGAGGCUCUUUGUUGUGCUGGUAGAAGCCCAUUUGCCCUUACUCUGGAUGUUCCAAAUGUUUCCCUUUCCAGGAGCUAGUCAGUCUUUCAGUCAUCUGUUUUAUAUGUCUCCUGCCUUCUCAGACAGUCCUUCUACUCUCUUUUAUUGUUCAUGAAAGACCUUCAAAUUGAAGUAAAGCCCAUAUUUCAAUAUAAAGAUAUGAAAGAAGGCUAAUAUCCUAUCAGUGAUAUUCUCAUCCAUCUUGUCAUGAAGGCCAUACCAUGAUAACUAUCACAUGUAAUGUAAAUUUGUUUAUUCAUCUCUCUUAUUCAUUUAUUCAUCUUUUUUCAUUUGUUUAUUCAUCUUUCUCCCAUUUGCUCCUGUCUUGAUUUAUCCACUAGCUCACUGAUUAUGCAAGCCUUGUAGUUCAUAUAUGUCAUGGGUUAACAUACAAUACAGCAUAUAUUUCAGACAUAAGUGUUUCAGAAAUAUUGUACAGAAGAUAUUGUACUCUAUUAAAAUGUGAUUCAGGGACAAGGGAGUGGUGCUUGGUGAUAAAAGUAUACUGCCAUAGUUGCUGAGGAAGGGCAGCAACAGAAAUCAGACUUCUAGUUGAUAUGGAUCUGGCAGGCAUCUCUGUCACACCCCUGGGAAAUAGUGGCCCAGGGCACAGAAGGAACCUGAAAUUAAAAUAUUUAGAUACAACCAAAACUCACUUGUCUGUCCCUAUGUAUACUGAAAAGUUUAGUGGGGCAUGCUGCUUUACCUGGCUUUGUGUUUUCACCAUUGUACUUAUUUUAUAUACCUAAUUGUACAUUUUAAGCAGCAGAUGACCUUGCAGCAAAAAUGUCUUGGUGUGAGAUGCAAAAUGAAUGAAAAACAACCACACCUAGGCUUUUGUCACUCAACCUAAACUACUCUUCAUGACCUGGAAAUGUUUUAUACUUAUGGGAAACUUUCUGCCCUUAACCUUAUAACUUCAGAUCCUUGUAUGAAUGGGUUUGGUUGUUUUUCUAUUAUAUAAAUUGUAGAUUGCAAGUACAAUGGGACAGUACAAAUCCCGGGACUCGGUAAAAUUAGAGUUGAAUGAUGAGGUGUCCAAAGGCAACGAAAACAUGGCAUAUUUCAAAUAAUGUUUUCCUUGCUUAUGUAACUUGGAGAAUUCACUCUAUUUGAUUGUGGGUUUCAAAGUAUUAGUGUUAAAAUUAGAGGUAGAUUUUCUGCCUGCUUACAAGACAAAUACAUAUUUAUCUCAUUAAAGAGGUCAUAAGCCUUUUUUUUAACCUUUAUAUUUCAAUACCAAUGGUGUAUUGUGGAUCUAACAUACACAGGCUUAAAUAAUUUCCUUUCCAUUUAAACUCAAUGUCUACCAAAUCUUGAUGAAAAGAUAAUUCUAGAAACUGAAGUCUUAAUUUUCUAACAAGUCAUGUCUUAAUUUCUUCUUCUCCCUCCCAAAUUUUCUGUUACCACUGAUCUUCAAACAGUACUUAAUCCUUUAAAACAAAAAGGUGUGUGUGUAUGUGCUGUGACAGUAAAAAUGAAAGAGAAAAAAUAGCUUCCCUAAAAGGUAGCCAGGCUUAUGGAAACAGUAUAAUAGGUGGCUAUAAAUGCCCUAUAGGCUUGUGUUACCACUAAAAAAUAACAAAAACCCAGAAAACGAGUACUCUCCUCAAAGGACAGUUUUAUCUUUUCCGUUUUGCAAUACAACUGUAAAUCUUCAUGCAUUAUCUGGUCUAUUUUAAUGGUGACCGCCUUACUAGUCAAGAAAAAACUGGAAAUAAAUGCCCAUAUUCCAGCCCUCUGUACCUCUGAGAUAGUAAAGCUUAAUACAGAAUUAAAACUGAAACUUUCUACCUUGCAGACUAAGUUUCUGUUAUUUUUAAGAUUUAUUGGAUUGCUCUUUGUAAAAGGUACCCCUACUUGUUUUCUUGUAUAGUUAUAUCACUGGGCUUAAUUCAAUGCAAUAAACACUAAUGUCAUGGCUUCUAUAAACUGUUAUCUCUAAGAUGGCUUUAGGCACAAAGUCUGAGUCGUCCAGUAACAGCUGUAAUUAGUUAGGGCCCUGAGGUCCAAGGUGGUAGUUACACUUCUCAUCUACAAAAAUAAAUAUCUUAUCUUAUUAAAGACAGGGUUCAUUUGUGUCAAGAAGUAGAGAUCCUUGACAAACAAACAAGACUUACUGUUAAUCACUAUGAUUUGAGUGCCAUUCCCUCGCCAAGAAAUUUUAGAAAAGCCCUUUUCAUAUCUGGACUUUUUUUGGGUAUAAACAAACAAAAAUUGUUAUUUUAAAGGAUAAACUUCAACCAUUGGAAUUUGGGGCAGUUUUUAUUCCUUAGCAUUUUCUUUGGUGAUGCCAUUACUUAGGAAGAAGUGCUGUGACAUUCAGCUGAUUAUUGGGUGUCACAGGACCUCUGUUCAGCCCUUCAGAUGACUAAAAUCUAAGACUAAACAGAAAUUGCUGUUAACAUAGAAGUACUUAAAAUGCAUUUCAUCCUAGUUGUUCUUAUAAUAGUGACAUUAUCGUAGACACAUUUUUAAAUCCAGAUAGUUAUUUGUACUUUUUCACACCAGUUUUUGCUUUUGUCACAUUUAUUCAAACUAGCACCUCCACAGUCAAAGUGUUGUCAUCCUACAGCCUCAAGGCCCCUCACUCUCAAUGUAUGGAAUGUCAUGGUACUUGAUGUUAUUGCAUGCCCAUUGCUGCAAGGCAUCACACAAGAUAUCCUGAGACAGGCGGUGUGCAUAUUCCAAGAUCACAGUAUUGGUCCCUGGAGGUUCCUUCACUUCCUCUUUGACAUUAACUGGAGAAGCCAUCCUAGGUAGACAUCUCUCUUCUGGCAUAAAGGGUUCUUCACUCUCAUGCUGCUUCUCACCUUCAUAUAUGGUAGGAAAUGGGAAAGUUUGCUUUGAUUUCAUGCAGCCCAUGUUAUGAAGAGCUGUUUGUGGAGGAAGCAGUGGCAAAGACUACUUCCAGGCCAUCUUUAGAAAACAAUGAAAUUUGUCCAUGUGAUGUUGACCAGUGCUUUCCCUCUCCAGGGCACUUCAGUAAUCAAUGUUCCCUUUCACCACUCUUCACGUGUAGUGUUUACCUGUCAAGAGAAGGUAGGUUUCAUUUUGAAGUUACAGAAUGCAAAAUAGUGUAUGAUUGAGUGGCAUGUAAAAAUCCUUUCAUCACUUUGGUCACAUGGAAGAAAUCUGAGGUAAAAACAAACAGCUUUAUCUUAUCAGUAGAAGAAAAAGAUAAUCACUCAAUAAAAAUGGCAACUUGCAAAAUAGGAAAACUUUUUUUCAAGAUCUUGCAUAUUUUAUAAAACUGAAAACAAUUCAAUUUUUGCUAGCUUAGAUUUAUCUAUACCAAAACAAUUCAAUUUUUGCUAGCUUAGAUUUAUCUAUACCAAGGGCUAGCAAACCAUUGGGCCAAAUUCCAGCUACCUAUUUUUGUACAGCCAUGCUCACGUGUUUACAUGUGUCCAUGGCUGCGUUCAUACUACAACAGCAGAACUGAAUAACUGUGACAGACCAUGUGGCCCACAAAGCUUAAAAUAUGUACUAUCUGACCCUUUACAAAAAAUGUUUGCUGAGUCCUGAUCUAUACUGUCAAGCAAAACAAGCACAUCAAAAUUUUGUUCCUCCCCAAACCUCAUGAACCUACAGAUCUUGGACUACUGUUAGAGUCUGGCUUUAUCCCCUGGUCACAUAUUUACAACUCAAAGAGUAGUAAACAAUGUUGGCUUUACUCUAGUGCCACGUCUAAACAAUAUAGGUUACAUAUAGCAAAGCCACCUAUUGACUGUUCCCUGUGAAAUUGUACAGAAGCUCAGAUUAAGGUUAAAGGUUUUUCCUCCUAAAUGUCUCAUUCCUACCCUUGUUUGAUGUUUGGUCAAUAAAUAGAUGACAAUGCUUGUGAUGUGCCUUCUAAGCCUCCCAAGUGUGUGUUAUCACAGAAUGAACUCCUCUUAAGGGACUUAAGGAUAACUAAAACAAUACAAGACAGCUUCAUUUUAAAGAGGACUGAGUGUAAGAAGCACAGGUAAUCUCUAUGAAUGAGAUUAAUGGUCCCUGAUUGUAUCUUAGUUUUGGGACUAAAAACAUAGCUCUAAAAAUUCAUAAAAUCUGUUUCUGAAAACACCUUUUUUUUUUUUUUUUUUUUUUUUGAGACAGGGUCUUACUCUGUUAACUCAGUCUGGAGUAAAGGAUGCAAUCACGGCUCACUGUAGCCUGGACCUCCUGGGUUCAAGUGAUCCUUCCACCUCAGCCCACUGAGUAGCUGGCCUGCAGGCACAAGUCACCAUGCCUACCUAAGUUUUUGUAGAGACAGGGUUUUGCCAUUUUGCCCAGGCUGGUCUUGAACUCCCGGGGUCAAGUGAUCUGCCCACCUCAGCCUCCCAAAGUGCUUGGAUUACUGGCGUGAGCCACUGUGCCUGGCCUGAAACCACUGAUCUUAAGGCAAAAGCUUGCGUGCAUCUAAUUCAUUUUUUAAUAGUUUGUAAUUAAGGAUGUCCAGAGGAGGUGAUGUUUGCCAGGUCUACCACCAUAUAUUAUUCUAUAAAUUCUACCCAGUUUCUCAUAAUACUACAUCUGUUCCUACCCCUAAUAAGAGUGAUAUGAGGGUAAGAAAGGAAAGGCAGUCUUCUGCUUUUAAUUACCUUUAGUUCUGUAUGCCCUGCUUCACGCUGCAUACUUCAGAGAUGUUAAUUUUAAAAGGGAAACAAGUUAUGUGUGGUGUCUGUCUUGUUUACUAGCCUGAACUGAAGAUGGGGACUGUCUUGGUUGUUAAUCAUCAGCAUGUUAUGAUUUUUCAUAGUGUCUAGUUUUUACUGUGAGGGAUGGUUAAGGGAAUUGGACAUGGUUAACCUGAAAAAAAUUACUUGGAGAACUCAAUGAGUGUCAGAUAAAUAAAAGGCUGUGAGUGGAACCAUCAGUGGAACCAUCAGAAUAUUCUGUUUUUUAAGACCUUUUGUUUUGCAAAAGCAGCUUUUUCUUACCCUAACAAAGUAGUGCCAGAUUUGUGCAUUUGCCAAAACCAGUUUUAAAACCAGACAAAAUAUAUGUUGCCAUUAUUUUCAGGCAUAGAGCAACAAGCAACACUGGAUUGUGAUCCCUGAGAGAAGAAAAACACAAGAUGUUAAAUCCCACAGAUGGUCAUUGUGGGAUUCUACCUGGGGGUAUCUCCCAGCAUUACCGUGGGAGUUGAGCCCCAGGAGAGUCAGAGAGUGGCAACUCUGAUGCAACAGAGGUUAGGGUUACUAAAACAGCUGGAAUUUAUAAGAUAGAGUUCAAGAUUGGGAAGAGAGGCAGAAAUCUGCAUGAGACUUGGCAAGGGUACUGGGAUGUGCAUGUCCAGGAUAAGGAUCUGCAAAGUGUUAGCAAACGAUUACUUCCUCUAGGACUUAAGAGUUGAACAGUGACACCAGAAGUUAUACAGUACUUAGAAUCCUUGGAAUUGCAGCCUGAGUGGAGCAAUCUCAUUGAACACUUUCGUAUUUAGUUACUACUCAAGAAAUGCGACACCUUAGGAAUCAGUAGUAUACCCUAAACAAGGUUUGGCAAGUGUUUUCUUAAAGGGCUAUGACUUAGGCUUGUGAGCUAGGAUGUUUGUGGCUUCUCCAAAUUCAUAUAUUGAAACCUAAUCCCCAACGUGAUGGUAUUUGGAGGUGGGGCCUUUGGGUGAUGAUAUUAGAGUUUUAGUGCUCUCAUAAAAGAGACCCCAGAGAGUUCCCUUGCCCCUACUGACAUGUGAGGCCACAGUGAAAAGCUGUAAACCACAAAGCAGGCCUUCACAAGACACCAUAUAUGCUCAUGCCUUAAACUUGGACUUCCCAGCCUCCAGAACCAUGAGAAAUAAAUCUGUGUGACUGAUUGAUAAACACCCAGUCUUCUAAAUACUCCAUACUAGUCUCUGGUAUUUUGUUAUACCAUCCUGAAUGGACUAAGACACAUAGGGUCUAUGUUACAACUACUCAGCUCUGCUAUUAUAGCACAAAAGAAGCCAGAUAAUAUAUUAAUAUUAAACAAAUGGGCAUGGCUAUAUCCAAUAAAGCUUCAUUUACAAAAAUAGCCAGCCUAUGGACCACAUUUGACUAAGUUCAAACAGAAAUAAUCCUCUUUAACAAGAAAUAAAACAAUACCAUUUAAAGGAAGAUAACAUAAGCCAGAUGCCUUACAAGGUAUUAUUCACAAUGCCUACCAUUCAAUUAAAAAAUUACUAGCCAUACAAAGAGGCAGGAAAAUCUGACCCAUAAUCAAGGGAAAAAAAAAAAAAAGACCCAGCAUUUCUUAAUAGAAAUUAAUAAUAGAACUUUAAAGUAGCUAUUUAAGUAUACCCAAGAAAAUAAAGGAAAAACUAGUGAACAAAAAAAGAAUCUCAGAGAAAUGGAAAUUGUAAAAUAAAAAUGGAAAAUCAGUAACUGAAAUGUACAAGAUGUGAAAUGAAAAAUUCAUUGUGUGGACUACUGAAUGUUGGAAAAGAUAGGAUUAGUGAACUUGAACAUAAAUCUAUAGAUGUGUCCAAUCUGAAAAAUGGAGGGAAAAGAUUUAAAACAUAGAGCAGCCACUAAAGAGAUAAUGCAAGUAUGACUUAUGAGGAAAGGAAUUAGAUACGUUUAACCCAGAAGAAGACAGGAAAGGAAGAACAUUGGGGGUUGGGGAGGGACAAUUAGAAAACCAACAUAUGAAAAAGCCUUCCAUGUGAAAAAUUACCUGAAAGAAAAUGGACUAAAAAUAACAAUUGAAAGGCAGAGAUGAUCAGACUAGUUUAAAAAUCCAAACCACACAUACAUAGUCUUUUCAACGAGUGCUGGAACAAACAAAUCAUCCAUAUGCCAAAAAAAAAAAAAAAAAAAAAGCUGGACACAGUUCUUAAACCCUUCACAAAAUUAAUUUGAAAUGGAUCAUAGACCUAAAUAUAAAAUAGGACUCCUAGAAGAUAACAUAGGAGACAAUCCAGAUAACCUUGGGUUUGGCGACAACCUUUUAGAUUCAGUGCCAAAGGCAUGAUGUGUUAAAGAAAUAAUUGAUAAGUUGGACUUCACUAAAAAACUGCUCUGUUUAAGACAUGGUCAAGAAAAUGAGAAGACAAGCCACAGACUGGGAGAAAAUAUUGCAAAAGCAUAUUUGAUAAAAGAUUGUUAUCUAAAGUAUACAAAGAACUUUUAAAAGUCAACAAUACAAAUAUGAACAAGCUAAUUGAAAAAUGGGCAAAAGAUCUGGACAGACACCUCACGGAAGUCUUCUUACAUAUAGGUGGCACAUAAACGUAUGGAAAAGUGUUCAACAUCAUGUCAUUCAGGAAUUGUAAAUUUAAACAGUGAGAUAAUGGCAAAAGCAACAGAACUCUCAUUCACUGUUGGUGAGAAUGCAAAAUGGUACGGUUACCUUGGGAGGACAGUCUGGCAGUUUCUUAGAAAGUGAAACAUUCUUACUGUAUGAUCCAGCAGUUCUGCUUCUUGGUAUUUACCCAAUAAGUUGAACGCUUAAAUCCAUGCAAAAAUCUGCAUAUGGAUGUCUGUAGCAGCUUUAUUCAUAACUUUGAAAACUUAGAAGCAAGCAAGAUGUCCUUCUUGGUGAAUGGGUAAACUGUGGCACAUCUAAACAAUGGAACAUAUUCAGCAUUAAAAAUAAAUGAGUUAGGCUGGGCAUAGUCACGCCUACAAUCCCAGCACUUUGGGAGGCUGAGGCGAGUAUCAUUUGAGCCCAGGAGUUCAAGACCAGCCUAGGCAACAUAGCAAGACCCCGUCUCUACAAAAAAAUUAAAUAUGAAAAAAAUUAGCCAGGCAUGGUGGUGCACACCUACAGUUUUAACUACUCAGGAAGCCGAGGUCACUUGGGCCCAGGAGUUGGAAUUGAAGGUUGUGGUAAGUUAAGAUUGAUUGCACCACUGCACUCCAGCCUGGGUGACUGAGCAAGACCCCACCUCAAAAAAUAAUAAUCCAGCCAUGGGAAGAAAAGGAGGAACCUCAAAUACUUAUUACUAAGUUAAGCCAAUCUGAAAGGGGUACAUGCUGUAUGAUUACAACUAUAUGACAUUCUAGAAAUGGCAAGACUCUGGAGACAGUAAAAAGACCAGUGGUUGCCAAGGGUUAUGGAAGAGGCUGAGAUGAAUAGGUGGAACAGACAAUUUUUAAGGCAAUGAAACUAUUCUAUAUGAUACUAAUAAUGGAUUUCUGUCAUACAUUUGUCAAAAACCAUAGGUUGUACAACACCAGGAAUGAACCCUAAAAUAACGUGGAUUUCAGGUGAUUGCGAUGUGUCUAGUGGGAGAUGCUGCGUGUGUGUGUGUGUGUGUGUGUGUGUGUGUGUGUGUGUGUGUAUACACAGGAUACGUGGGAACACUACUUCCUGCUCCAUUUUUCUGUUAACUUAAAACUGCUCUGAAAAACAGUCUAUUAUUUUUUUAAAAAAUACACCCACUAUAUGCUAUCUAUAAAAGAUACACAACUUAAAACUGACAAACCCACAAGCAUAGCUGGAGACUUAAAACAUUACUAGAAUAGUCAAAGAAAAAAUACGUGUUCUGAACAACAUUAUGCUCCAACUUGAGUUGAUAUUCACAGAACACUACACCCAACAACUAUUACAUAUUCUUAUCAAGUGCAUAUGGAACAUUCACCAAGAUAGACUAUUGGUAGUCUCAGCAGAUUUCAAAGGCUUAAAACAUUACACAGUACAAUUUCUAACCACCCCAGAGAGUAAAAUAUCUAGAAAAGCCUCAUAUAUUUGGAAACUAAACAUAUUUCUAAAUAACCCAUGGGACAAAGAAGAAAAUCACAGGAGAAAUUAAAAUAUAGUUUCAACUAAACAAAAGCCAAAACAUCAAAAUUUUGAAAUGCAUUAGUUUUAGAGCUUAGAAGGAAAUUUAUAUACUUAAAUGCUUAUAAUAGAAAAGAAGAAAAGUUUAAAUCAGUGAUAUAAGCUUUCACCUUAAGCUAAAAAAAGAAAAGCAAAUUAAACCCAAAAUAAGUAGACAGAAGUAGGUAAGAACAGAAAUCAGUGAAGCAUACGAUAGAGACAACAGAAUGAAUGCUGGUUCUUUAAAAAGAUCUAAUAGAUACAUCUCUAUACAGACUGAUCAAGAAAAGUCACAUAUUAAGAUGUGUAAUGGGCAUUAUGACAUCUAUAUACGUUUAAAAGGCAAACAGGAAUAAUAUAAACAAUUUUAUGCCAAUAUCAAAUUACCAAAAUUGGCACAAGAAAAAAAUGAUAGCCCUACAUCAAUUAAAGAAAUUGUAAAUCUUUCCAAAAAGAAACCUCCAGGCCCUAAUGGCUACACUAGAGAACUCUUACCAAGGCCAUUACGAGGAAGUAAUACCAGUCUUAUCUAAACUCUUCAGAAAAGAGAGAAAGAGGAAAGAAAGAUUUCCCGAAUUAUUCUAUAUGAGGCCAGUAUUACCAAGAAGACAAAACUCCACAGGCCAAUAUCCCUCAUGAACAUAGACCCAGAAGUUGGCAAAUUGAAUCUAACGUGUAAAAUGGAUAAAACAUGAUGACUGAGUGGAUUUAUACCAGAAAUUCAAGGAUAUUCCAAAGACAAUAGAUAUAAUUCACUAUAUUAACAUAAAAAAAAUCAGAUGAUCACCUCAGUAGAAACAGAAAAAAAAUUUUGAUAAAAUACCAUUUUUUAUUUUUAAAAUCCCAGCAAAGUAUUAAUAGGAAGGCCUUCCUCAAAAGUAAUGUUAGUGGUGAAAGACAACACUUUUUCCCUAUGACAGGAGCAAGGCAGCAAUAGUCAUUCUCAUGAUUUCUGUUUGAUAUUUUACCGGAAGUCCCACUGAGUAUGAGGAAGGGAAGACAUACAAAGCAUAAAGAUUGAGAGAAGGAGAAAACUGCCAUUAUUUGCAGAUGACAAAAUUGUAUAGAGAAAAUUUUAAAGAUUAUAUGGCCUCCCCCCAAAAAAAAUUUACUGGAAUAAUUGUAGCAAGGUCUUAACAUAUAAAAGUGACAUAUAAAAAGUAAUUUCUACAAACUUAGCAGAAGAUGAAAUUAAUGCCAUUUGCAAUAGCAUCAAAAACAUGAACACUUAGGGAUAAAUUUAACAAAGCAUAUGAAGGAAAACUGCAUUUUGUAUUGUGUACGUUGUACGUGAAAAAUACAAAAUGUUACUGAGAAAAAGUAAAGAACCUAAACAAACAGACAAAUGCUGUUCAUGAUCUGAAAGACAAUAUUCUUAGUCCUCCCCAAAUUAACAUGUAUAUUCGGCAAAAUUCCAGCAGGCUUUUCUGUAGACAUUGACAAAUGGAUUCUAAAAGUCCAGUCAAAAUCCCAGCAGGAUUUGUUUUAUAUAUAUAGAUAUAUAGAUACACACACACACACACACACACACACACACACACACACAGAUUCUGAAUUAUACAUGGAAACACAAACUAGAAUGGCCAAAACAAUUUUGAGAAAGAACAAUAAUUUGGAGUACUCCUAUUAUCUAAUGUUAAGAAUGACUAUAAAGCUACAGUAAUUAGUGCUAUAUUGACAAAAGGCUAGCCACAAACCUAUGAAACAGAAACAAGUCCAGAGAUACACCCAUAAAAAUAUGGUAAACUGAUACUUGACAUGUCCAAAAACAAUGAAUGCAAAAAGGAUAAUCUUUUCAACAAAUGGGAUUGGAACAAUUGGACAUUCACAUACUCUCCCCCCACCAAAAUCUACUUAUACCUUAUACUUUAUAGAAAAAUUAACUCAAAAGGGAUCAUAGUUUUAAAUGUAAAAUGUAAAACUAUAAAACAAGAAGACAAAACAUUUGCGAUCUUGGGUUAGGAAAAGAGUUCUUAGAUGUGAUACCAAAAGCAUGAACCAUGAAAGAAAAAAACUGGUAAACUAGACUGAAUCAAAAUGAAAAAGAUUUGCUCUGGAAAAAAAAACACAGUUAAAAGAUUGAAAAAAAAACAGCAAAUAUAAAAAAUAUUUGCAAGUCAUCAUCUAGCCAAUAAAUGACUUGAAUCCAGAAUAUAUAAGUAUCAAAACUCAAUAGCAAGACAACAACCCAGUUUAGAAAACGAGAUUUGAAAGAUUUAGGCAGUUCACUUGGUACCACCUAUAGAUAGCAAAUAUAAGUACAUGAAAGAUGCUCAAUAUCAUUAGCCAUUAGGGAAAUGCAAAUUACAGCCAUGAUAAGAAACCACUAUGUAGCUGUUAGAAUGGGUAAAAAUAAUACCAAGUGCUGGUGCAUAUACAGAGCAACUGCACUCUCAUACAUUGCUGGUGGGAAUGCAAAAUGACAUGGCCUCUGGAAAAGUUUGGCAGUUUCUCACAAAGUUGGAAUAACCACAUAGAAGACCCAGCAAUCCCACUCCUAGAAAUUUACCCUAGAUACAUGAAAAUUUGUGUUCACAUAAAAAAAUUGUAUGCUGGCUGGGGACGGUGGCGCAUGCCUGUAAUCCCAGUAUUUUGGGAGGCCUUGGUGGGUAGAUCACCUGAGGUCAGGAGUUUGAGACCAGCCUGGCCAACAUGGUGAAACUCUGUCUCUACUGAAAAUACAAGAAAGUUAGCAGGGCAUAGUGGUGCACACCUGUAGUCCCAGCUGCUUGGGAGGCUGAGGCAUGAGAAUCACCUGAAUCCAGGAGGCAGAACAGAGGUUGCAGUGAGCUGAGAUCACGCAACUGCACUCCAGCCUGGGUGACAGAGUGAGACUCCAUCUCAAAAAAUAAAGAAAAAAAAUUGUAUGCAAAUGUCUGUCACAGCUUUAUAAUUGCCAAAAGUUGACAACAAAGAUGUUAAUGUACACCAAUAUGGAUGACUCAAAGGCAUGCUGAUUGAACAAGCUAGUCUCAAAAGGUUACUUAUUUAUAUGACAUUCUGGAAAAAGGCAAAACUAUAGGGACAGAUGAUAGAUUAGUGGUUGACAGGAGGUUGGGGGUAGACUGUGACCAAAAGGGCAGCAGGAGGGACCUUUUUUGGAGUGAUGUAACUAUUCUUUAUCCCGAUUGUGGUGGUGGCUGUAACAAAUCUAAACAUGCGUUAAAAUUCAUAGACUUGUUCACCAAAAUGAAGUCAGCUUUACUGUAUGUUAAAAAUUUUAAAAAGGUAUUUUUUAAAACCACAAUAUAAUUACCCACACUAAGAUUGCUAAAAUUUAAAAAACCCCAGUGCUUAGUGUUGGUGAGGACAUGCAACGCAUAUAUUGCUGGAAGGAAUGUAAAAUGGUACAACCAUUUUAAAGAAUUCCUUGGCUGUUUCUUAAAAAGUUAACCACACACUUACCCUGUGAACCAGCCAUUUCAUUUCUAGAUAUUUAUCUAAGACAAAUGGAAACACAGGUAUUUUAAAAAUCUGUAUACCAAUAUCCAUAGCCUCUUUAUUCACAAUAGUCAAAGCUGGAAACAACCCAAAUGUCCAUCAGUAGGCAAAUCAAAUGGAUAAACAAAUUAGGGAUAUCCUCAAAAUGGAAUAUAACUUGACAAUUAAAAAAGGAUGAACUAUUGGUAUGUCAAACCACAUGGAUGAAUCUCAGACAUGUUGAGCCAGAUAAAAAAGAUGGAUCAUAUUUAUAUGAAUUUCAAGAUUGGACAAUAGUGACCCUAUGAAUAGAAAUCAUAGUAGUGAUUCCCUUUGGGUGGGAAGAAGUAAGGACUGUUUGGAAGAGGCCCUGAAAUAACUUUCUAGGCUAUUAAAAAAUUCUAUAUCUUAAUUGGUAUGUUAGUUACAUGAGGUAUAUGUUAAAACAUGUUAGAUUGUACCUUUAACAUCUGUUUACUGUAUUUCACUGUAAUUUUUACUUUAAUAAGAUAUAAGAACAGUUUUUGAGAACAUUCUGGGGCACCUAAAUCCAGGGGACUGAUGUAUUUUAUCUGAAAAAGACCGCCUAUGGGCAGCAUCCAGAGCGGACCAGCUCCCUGUGCUGGAGGACUCCAGUGUGAGGCCUGCUGCUUCCUUUCUACAUUGGCCUGAAACCAGCCCAACUCAGUGGUCAUAAUCUUCUGGGCCUACCGAAGAGCAAAAGCCUACUUCUAGUUCUUCCAGUUGCCAGUUCAAGGGCUUUAUCUGUCACUUCCUUUGGGAACAGGUAGAGUGCUUUGAUUUAGAAUGAUGGCAAUAAAUGAGAAACCAAUUUGAAAUUGGA